GCCGCCAUCGCUCUCCCGGGCUUAGAAGGCCCGGCUACUGACGCGCAGUGCCAGACCUUACCCCUCACGGUCCUUAAGUCUCGGUCGCCCUCGCCUCGCAGCCUGCCACCCGCGCUCAGCUGCCCGCCUCCUCAGCCAGCCAUGCUGGAGCAUCUGAGCUCGCUGCCCACGCAGAUGGAUUACAAGGGCCAGAAGCUAGCUGAACAGAUGUUUCAGGGAAUUAUUCUUUUUUCUGCAAUAGUUGGAUUUAUCUACGGGUACGUGGCUGAACAGUUCGGGUGGACUGUCUAUAUAGUUAUGGCCGGAUUUGCUUUUUCAUGUUUGCUGACACUUCCUCCAUGGCCCAUCUAUCGCCGGCAUCCUCUCAAGUGGUUACCUGUUCAAGAAUCAAGCACAGACGACAAGAAACCAGGGGAAAGAAAAAUUAAGAGGCAUGCUAAAAAUAAUUGAGGUUUUCAUGAUUCAGCACCUGCUUUUGUUUCUGUGAGAUGAGCUAAAUUGCUUUCAUACCCCAGAUAAGAGCUAAAACCACCUAAUGCUCUUAUGGCACAGCUGUGUAUAGAUUUAGUUCUCUUUAUACUUCAUUUCUAGCCCAGUUGGGUUUUGAUUUAUAUAAGUAGUUUAGACCUUCUCUUCAUAAUCUUGCUCUGAGAUGGGGAACAGAACACACAAGUAUGAAGUUUCUUUCAGGUGUAAAUAAUGAAAAAUAAAUGCCUCAUAAAUGAUAGUACAAUGUAACUAUCAAAGUUUUAUAAUUCAUUAUGAGUUAACCAUUUUAAUGUUUCCAAUUAAACCUCAUAGUGCAAGUUCUUUGUCUAAAGGGUCUUCUGUUGAUUAUUCUGCAAGGAAGAUAAUUAAUAAAAGCCUAAGUUAGAAGUUCGUGCUUCUGGCCAGGUGCAGUGGCUCUCACCUAUAAUCCCAGCACUUGAGGAGGCUAAGGCAGGAGGAUGACUUGAGCCCAGGAGUUUGAGACAUUUCAUGGUAUGUAAUUAAUAGUUGUCAUUAGAACAUUAGUUCCAUGAGAACGGGGACUUUGUUUUGCUCACUGCUGUCUACCCAGUACAUAGAAGAGUACACGAUGCAUUGUUAAGUACUUAAGAUUUAUUGAAUGAGAACUGCAUUGUACAAUAUGGUGCCACUAGACACGUCUAUUUAAUUAAAAUUAAAAUAUAAAACUCUAAAACUAGCCAUGAUUCAAAGGUUCAAUAGCUAUAUGUGACUAGUGGCUACCAUAUAAAACAUUUCCAUCACAAAGUUCCAUUUAUCAGAUCUUAUAUAGAACCUUGAAUAAAAUUUAAUAGACAAGUGAUUUUGUAUUUAACAUUUCACCUUUAUUGAAUGCCUAUAAGGCCAUUUGAAUAACGGAUCAUGUACAAAGCAACAGGAAAAAAAAAACUGCAAGCAGUAAAGGUUGUGCAGGUGAUAUUCAGUAACACUGCAGUGUAGCCAGAGCAAGGACAUAAAACUUCCUUAGCUUUGUAAGUCUGUGGAAAUCAAAACUUCUAAAAGAGAAAACCGAAAUCAGAAUUACUGACACUUUAGGCCAGGCAUGGUGCCUCAAGCCUGUAAUCCCAGCAUUUAGGGAGGCCAAGGCAGGCAGAUCACCUGAGGUCAGGAGUUCAAGACCAGCCUGGCCAACAUGGUGAAACUCCAUCUCUACUAAAAAUAACGAAAAUCAGCCAGGCAUGGUGGUGUGUGCCUGUAAUCCCAGCUACUCGGGAGGCUGAGGGAGGGGAACUUGAACCCAGGAGGCGUAGGCUGCAGUGAGCCAAGAUCGCACCACUGUACUCCAGCCUGGGCAACAAGAAGACUCCAUCUCAAAAAAAAAAAAAAAAGAAUGAUUGACAUUUUAGAACCAAUGCCAAAAGAGUAACACAUCAAAGUCUCUGAACUGUGGCCAAAGGUAUAUUCGGAAGAAAAUUCACAGUCUUAAAGAUGAGUUUUUAAAUUAAUUUAGGAAGAUGAAUUAAGCACUCAAGUAAAAACGAUAAAAGUGGGAAGAAAAGAUGUUUAAACAAAAUAAAAAUAUACAGUAUGGUAAUUAAUAAGAAAGUAUGGGGGAAGUCAGGUGUGGUGGUUCAUGCCUAUAAUCCCAGCACUUUCAGAGGCCGAUGCAGGAGGACUGCUUGAAUGCAGUUUGAGACCAGCCUGGGCAACACAGACUUCCUCUCCACAAAAAAUUUUAAAAAUUAGCCAGGUGUGGUGGUGCAUGCCUGUGGUCCUAGCUACUUGAGGGGCUGAGGUGGGAGGAUCACUUAAGCCCAGGAGGUCAAGGCUGCAGUGAGCUAUGAUCACCUCACUGCACUCCAGGCUGGGUGACAGAGCAAGACCCUGUCUCAAAAAAAAAAAAAAAAAAAAAAGAUAUGGGUGAGAUUCCUUUAAUUCUAAUAAAAUACCUACUUUAUACCAAUACAUUAGAAAAAUUAAGUAAAACUGAUGACUCUCCAGAACGAUGUGGAUUUCCAAAACAUGCACGGAAAGGUGAAUAGCUCAAGGAUACCAAGUUUGCCAAAGAUUUGUUCCCAACUGGGCAUUGGGACUUGAUGGUUUUGCAAGUUGAGUUCUAGCAAACCCUUCAAAGUGAAAAUAAGAGUUAUCAGAAACCAGGCUGUGAGCACUGUAAAAGGGCAGGAAGUAUUGUUUUAUUCACCACUAUAUCCCCAGCUCCUGGCAGAGAACCUGGCACACAGUAAACUCUAAAUAAAAAUCUGUUAAGUGUGCCGGGCGCGGUGGCUCACGCCUGUAAUCCCAGCACUUUGGGAGGCCGAGGCGGGCAGAUCACGAGGUCAGGAGAUUGAGACCAUCCUGGCUAACACGGUGAAACCCUGUCUCUACUAAAAAAAUACAAAAAAAUUAGCCGGGCAUGGUGGCGGGCAACUGUAGUCCCAGCUACUCGAGAGGAUGAGGUAGGAGAAUGGAGUGAACCUGGGAGGCGGAGCUUGCAGUGAUCUGAGAUUGGGCCACUGCACUUCAGCCUGGGUGACAGAGCAAGACUGUGUCUUAAAAAAAAAAAAAAAUUGUUAAGUGGCUGUAAAGGGAACAUUUCAUUAGAGUAUUUGUGUGUGUGUGUAAUUUUCAAAGAUAGAUAUAUUUUUAGUUAUAGAAACUGAAAACAGGGCUGGGCACAGUGGCUCAUUCCUGUAAUCCUGGCACUUUGGGAGGCUGAGGUGAGUGGAUUGCUUGAGCCCAGGAGUUCUGAGAUCAGCCUGGGCAAUGUGGUGUAACCCUGUCUCUACAAAAAAUACAAAAACUAGCCAGGUGUGGUGGCACACGCCUGUGGUCUCAGCUACUAGGGAGGCUCAGGCAGGAAUACCACUUGAGCCCCAGAAGUGGAGGUUGCAGUGAGUUGAGAUCAUGCCACUGCACUCCAGCCUGACUGACAGAGUGAAACUCUGUCUCAAAAAAAAAACACCUGAAAACAUUUCUGGAGCAAUAUUUAUUUUUAGAGUCCCUCGAAUACAGAAGUGAAAAUGUACUAUUCAAGACUUGUAUUUAACUUCAUAAAAUUUCUUUCCUAGAUGGGUAUUACCUCUUAUUAAACAACUAAUAAAAUAUGUGCUAUAUAAUCAUACAUUUAAAACAUGGAAAGACAACUAAUAUCUUACAGUACAUGAAGACAAACUUCAGGAGACAAACAUUAAAUAUAUCCAAAAACUAAAUGGACCUGGACUUUGCUUACAAAUUGCUUAAAUGGAAAUGAAAUUUGUGUUUAAGAAAUGUUUUCACUGAUGGAAAAAUAAAUCUAACAAAACCAUUAUGUAAAAACAUACUGAUUUACAAAGCCAA